GAAAAGUGCGCCCUACGAAAGGACGGUCGACUUCGGCGGGGCCCAGGUGAGAAAGGCCCACCUGUGUCCUGGUUGAGGGUCUCCAGGGUUCUUUGGGGCCCGAGGAUUCCUGAAAUUGUGGAUCACCCACCUAUGCUUUAAGACAUGCUUUAUUUUUUUUUUUUCUGGAAGCCCUGCAACUUCCCUAAAAAUUGAAUGAAUUGUAGAACAGACCUAUGGAAUUUCAGACCUGAACAAUCAGGUGGACAACUUCUUGUGACUUUGGGUAUUCUGAAAUUACUCAUCUUGACUCUACUGUGCCUGGAUGUAGCUGUGUGUUUUGUGUGUAUCCUGUUCAUGGCCAAUGGUGGCAGAGUCUACAUAGAACUAUGCUUCGUGGUGUUCUGGGGAAAACCUUUCGACUUGUUGGCUAUACUAUUCAAUAUGGCUGUAUAGCUCAUUGUGCUUUUGAAUACGUUGGUGGUGUUGUCAUGUGUUCUGGACCAUCAAUGGAGCCUACAAUUCAAAAUUCAGAUAUUGUCUUUGCAGAAAAUCUUAGUCGACAUUUUUAUGGUAUCCAAAGAGGUGACAUUGUGAUUGCAAAAAGCCCAAGUGAUCCAAAAUCAAAUAUUUGUAAAAGAGUAAUUGGUUUGGAAGGAGACAAAAUCCUCACCACUAGUCCAUCAGAUUUCUUUAAAAGCCAUAGUUAUGUGCCAAUGGGUCAUGUUUGGUUAGAAGGUGACAAUCUACAGAAUUCUACAGAUUCCAGGUGCUAUGGACCUAUUCCAUAUGGACUAAUAAGAGGACGAAUCUUCUUUAAGAUUUGGCCUCUGAGUGAUUUUGGAUUUUUACGUGCCAGCCCUAAUGGCCACAGAUUUUCUGAUGAUUAGUAAGCAUUUAUUCUUUUGACUUGAUUAUUGUCUCCUUUUCAUGUGAAUUUAUUACUCCCGUUGAAACCGUGUACUUACCAAUAAACUAUUUGCUAUUCA